ACACUAUAAAUGUCUUUCCUUAUCUGUGUGUACUCUUAUCUCACUGUUCUAUUUUUUCUCCUCAUUUAUAUUAACUCUUUCUUACCUUUUUUUCUGAACUUCUAGGCCUUCUCUUUCCAGAACUGGUGGAAGACAAAUGAAACGGCCAAGAUGGUAAGAAACAAGCCGCAUUUCUCCUUGGGGAGACUGAUAAUUUAAAAGGUUUGUUGUGUCAGAAACAUUCCCAGCUUCAUCACCAACCCUUUCCUUCCACCUCUGCCCACUGGAGACCACUUAUAUCCCGAAGCGGACGCGGCAGCUGAAGUCAGGAAACCAUGCAUCACAUUAGCAGGAGCCAACUGCAGACUUUAAACUCCGUUCAACAUGUGGAUGCGGCAGAGAAAUGACCUGUCCAGACAAGCCGGGGCAGCUCAUAAACUGGUUCAUCUGCUCCCUGUGCGUCCCGCGGGUGCGUAAGCUCUGGAGCAGCCGGCGUCCAAGGACCCGGAGAAACCUUCUGCUGGGCACUGCGUGUGCCAUCUACUUGGGCUUCCUGGUGAGCCAGGUGGGGAGGGCCUCUCUCCAGCAUGGACAGGCGGCUGAGAAGGGGCCACAUCGCAGCCGCGACACCGCCGAGCCAUCCUUCCCUGAGAUACCCCUGGAUGGUACCCUGGCCCCUCCAGAGUCCCAGGGCAAUGGGUCCACUCUGCAGCCCAAUGUGGUGUACAUUACCCUACGCUCCAAGCGCAGCAAGCCGGCCAAUAUCCGUGGCACCGUGAAGCCCAAGCGCAGGAAAAAGCAUGCAGUGGCAUCGGCUGCCCCAGGGCAGGAGGCUUUGGUCGGACCAUCCCUUCAGCCGCAGGAAGCGGCAAGGGAAGCUGAUGCUGUAGCACCUGGGUACGCUCAGGGAGCAAACCUGGUUAAGAUUGGAGAGCGACCCUGGAGGUUGGUGCGGGGUCCGGGAGUGCGAGCCGGGGGCCCAGACUUCCUGCAGCCCAGCUCCAGGGAGAGCAACAUUAGGAUCUACAGCGAGAGCGCCCCCUCCUGGCUGAGCAAAGAUGACAUCCGAAGAAUGCGACUCUUGGCGGACAGCGCAGUGGCAGGGCUCCGGCCUGUGUCCUCUAGGAGCGGAGCCCGUUUGCUGGUGCUGGAGGGGGGCGCACCUGGCGCUGUGCUCCGCUGUGGCCCUAGCCCCUGUGGGCUUCUCAAGCAGCCCUUGGACAUGAGUGAGGUGUUUGCCUUCCACCUAGACAGGAUCCUGGGGCUCAACAGGACCCUGCCGUCUGUGAGCAGGAAAGCAGAGUUCAUCCAAGCAGCAGCAGCAGCGUGUCUUUCCAUGCGCUUGGCAUUCUUUAUUUUCCCAGCCUGGGAGGAUAUGAGAGUUCCAGGGAAAUGCUGUAUUGGACAUGCAAGACUCACCUGGGGAACUUAUCAGCAGUUGCUGAAACAGAAAUGCUGGCAGAAUGGCCGAGUACCCAAGCCUGAAUCGGGUUGUACUGAAAUACAUCAUCAUGAGUGGUCCAAGAUGGCACUCUUUGAUUUUUUGUUACAGAUUUAUAAUCGCUUAGAUACAAAUUGCUGUGGAUUCAGACCUCGCAAGGAAGAUGCCUGUGUACAGAAUGGAUUGAGGCCAAAAUGUGAUGACCAAGGUUCUGCGGCUCUAGCACACAUUAUCCAGCGAAAGCAUGACCCAAGGCAUUUGGUUUUUAUAGACAACAAGGGUUUCUUUGACAGGAGUGAAGAUAACUUAAACUUCAAAUUGUUAGAAGGCAUCAAAGAGUUUCCAGCUUCUGCAGUUUCUGUUUUGAAGAGCCAGCACUUACGGCAGAAACUUCUUCAGUCUCUGUUUCUUGAUAAAGUGUAUUGGGAAAGUCAAGGAGGUAGACAAGGAAUUGAAAAGCUUAUCGAUGUAAUAGAACACAGAGCCAAAAUUCUUAUCACCUAUAUCAAUGCACACGGGGUCAAAGUAUUACCUAUGAAUGAAUGACAAAAGAAUCUUCUGGCUAGGGUGUUAGAUAUAUUUAUGCAUUUUUGGUUUUGUUUUUAAAUCAAGCACAUCAACCUCAAGCCCGUUUAGCAAUGAGGCAGUGUAGAUGAAUACGUAAAAUAAAUGACUUUAACCAAGUAGCUAUAAUGGGACUUAGCACUGUAUGCAUACUUAAAAAGGUUUUGAAAAACAAACUACUUGAGAAAUAUUUGUUUAUAUUUUUCUCUAACAUCAUGCUAUGUGUCAGUCUGAACAUCUGACAACAGAAAUUUCAGUUAUUAUUCUAGCUAAGUUUUGAAAACAUUUGUCAUGCUGUUUAAUAGAAAACUGCAAACCAGAGACACUGACUCCAUUAAUAAACCAUAUUUUGUGCCGUUUUGACUGUUCUGACCAAAUACUAAUGGGAACAAUUCUUGACGUUUUUCUGUUGCUGAUUGUUAACAUAGAGCAGUCUCUACACUACCCUGAGGCAACUCUACAUUGGAACACUGAGGCUUACAGCCUGCAAGAGCAUCAGAGCUGACCAUACAUUUAAACAGAAAUGCUGGUUUAUUUGCAAAAUCACCAGUAUAUUUUCUAUUGUGUCUAUAAAAAAUCAGUCAUUUAAGUACAAGAAUCAUAUUUUCCAUUCCUUUUUAGAAAUUUAUUUUGUUGUCCCUAUGGAAAUCAUUCACAUCUGACAAUUUAUAUGUUAAAGAGUUUUACUCUCUCUAUUUUGGUCCAAUUUGUAUCUAGUGGCUGAGAAAUUAAAUAAUUCUAAAGUAUGAAGUUACCUAUCUGAAAAUGUACUUACAGAGUAUCAUUUUAAAAUGGAUGUCUCUUUAAAAAUUUUGUUACUUUUACCAACAAUGUAAUAUAAUUUAUGUAUAUUUUAUUAAUAAUAGUGAAUUCCUUAAAAUUUGUUCUAUGUACUUAUAUUUAAUUUGAUUUAAUGGUUACUGCCCAGAUAUUGAGAAUUGGUUCAAAUAUUGAGUGUGUUUCAAUAUAUUAUCUGGCUUAUUUCAACAUGAGUAAUAUGAGCAAAAUAAGUUAAAACCUGCGUCUGAUCAAUUUUCCUCAUGACUAGAACUAAAACAGUAAAUUUGGACAAUAUUAAGCCUCAAAUAAUCAUCUCCAAACUCCUUCUAACACUUUUUAAAUCAGAUUGGAAGACAUGGACAAAUCAGGUUCAUGUGUUGCAUCUUUAUGUCCUUUGCCAAUAUCCAAGAUCAUCACAUAUGGUAGAUAUUCACAUGGAGUUUCAAAUUCAGAAUAGAUUACCAUUACCUUCCUGCCCUUACACAUCCUACUCCUUAUUUAAAAGUUCUAUUUGUGACUUUUCAUUUCCUGAAAGUUUAAAAAUACAAUUUGAGAAUGUUUAUAAUACAUUCUCUCCUGUCUUUUCACGGUUACGUCUGUUAUUGCUGAAAUACACCACAUUUUCUUUGUUCUGGUCAAGGUUAACUCAAUAUCUGUGUGAAAGAGAACUACUAACAACGUUACAAUAGAGGCUAGAUUUGAAAAAAAAAAUCUAUAGAUCUAAUUGAUACAAUUGUAGAACAAAAUGUCAAAAUAAUGUUUUAAGUAUAAGAGAAGAUGGACCAAGGAGAGAGAGAUCAUUUGAAAAUCUAAUUGUAGCUUUUCUAGGCUCACAUUCAUGUACUACUUUUAGCACCCUUAUGGGCUGUGCUCGCCCCCUGGACAGUUGAGCUUUGGAUUAUCUUCCUCUUCAAUUUUCCCUCUAUUGACCCGAGUGUCUCCCUCUGCUUCUACAGAUUUAUAGUACUCCUUGGCUCUUUUGAGUCUCCACUUUUACUCACUGUCUCUGGGAUUUUUAAGAUCCUUUUCUUCUCUUAUAAAUCAUCCUCUUAAUGAAAAUUAGCCUAACAAAAGUUUGGAGACUGGAAUCCUACUUUGAGCCACUGACUUGAAAUAACUCUUUUGGCAAGUUGCCUGACAUCCUGUCUUACCAAGGUGGCAUAUUUGCAUUUUUACUGCUUAAAACAUUUUUUUUUUUUUACCAUCUUUAUCCAAAUUUAUCAUAUUGAUGGUAGGACUAACAGGCUUUUUAGAAGCUGGCUUUAACUUUGAGUCUCAAGCUACAAUGCUGUUGGGCAGCCUGGUCUUCCCACGUGAGGGUUUAACUUUGUUUAUUUGCCUCCAGUUAUUCCAAAAUGCUUAUUAAAUGAAAGUCCCAGGAACAUGUUUAUUUUAGUCACCUUUGCUUUUUAACAAUUUUGUUUUGUAAUCAAUGAGUAAUUCAUGAUGAAUUAUUUUUGACUAAUGGAUAGCCGAAGGCCAGGCUUUUAAUUCUAAUAGGUAAUGUUCUUCUUUUGUCUUAUUGAAACAAUGAGAAUACUCUGUGCAUUUCAAAUGCACUCCGAUUAUGCUGUGGUUUUAUUCACAUAAGCACAAUAUGUGUUUUAUUUAUAACUUCAUAACAAACUUAUAAUAUAAUAAUUUACCUUAGCAGACAUGCAAAAGCUUAUUCUUGUGUGACUUACUUUCUUUAAGCUAAUAAUAUAAAAAUAAAUAUGUAUCUUAAAAAUCUAUAAUAAAACAUUAGAAAUUAAAGAUAUGUGCUUUUUAUUUUGCAGAUGAGUUCAUUUGCUUUUGUAGAUGUGUUUUCAGAGCUAGGUACAGAGGAAUGUUUGCUACCUUUAGCGGUGAAAAAAGAAAGAGAGUCAAGAAUUUUGUUGGAUUGUGUUUGUGUGUGCAUAUAUUUGAUAUCAUCAUUAUAUUUGUAAUCUUUGGACUUGUAAUCAUAGCCUGUUUAUUCUACUGUGCCAUUAAAUAUACUUUACCUUAUACAUAACGAAUAAAAUACCUAGAAGUAGAUUUAUUUACACACUGUCUUAUGAAAUUCUUAUGUUUAUGUCAGCACAGAACAAGCACACAUUUAGAGCAUUCAUCUGAAAAUUAUAUGGAAAUUGAACAUGGGUCAAAUAAAGAUG